AGCGCCUUGGACCCGUUGGACGCCCACCAUGCCGCCCCGAGGGCCAGCCUCUGAGCUGCUGCUGCUGCGGCUGCUCCUGCUGGGGGCGGCCACCGCUGCUCCCUUGGCACCGAGACCCUCCAAGGAGGAGCUGACCCGCUGUCUGGCAGAGGUGGUCACAGAGGUGCUGACCGUGGGCCAGGUCCAGAGAGGACCCUGCACUGCUCUUCUCCACAAGGAGUUGUGCGGGACAGAGCCCCACGGCUGUGCGUCCACCGAGGAGAAAGGCCUGCUGCUUGGGGAUUUCAAGAAGCAGGAGGCUGGGAAGAUGAGGUCCAGCCAGGAGGUGAGGGAUGAGGAAGAGGAGGAGGUAGCAGAGAGGACCCACAAGUCUGAGGUCCAGGAACAAGCCAUCCGCAUGCAAGGGCAUCGCCAGCUCCACCAGGAGGAGGACGAGGAGGAGGAGAAGGAGGAGAGGAAGAGGGGGCCCAUGGAGACCUUUGAGGACCUGUGGCAGCGGCAUCUAGAGAAUGGAGGGGACCUCCAGAAGCGGGUGGCAGAGAAGGCCAGUGACAAAGAGACGGCCCAGUUCCAGGCAGAGGAGAAGGGGGUGCGGGUGCUGGGCGGGGACCGCAGCCUGUGGCAGGGGGCCGAGAGAGGCGGAGGAGAGAGGCGCGAGGACUUGCCCCACCACCACCACCACCACCACCAGCCAGAGGCUGAGCCCAGGCAGGAGAAGGAGGAGGCUUCGGAGAGGGAGGUGAGUAGGGGGAUGAAGGAGGAACACCAACACAGUUUGGAGGCAGGGUUGAUGAUGGUCAGUGGAGUCACAACUCACAGCCACCGGUGUUGGCCCUGCACCACCAGAUCCAUCACUAGUGGAUCACAGUGGCCAAGACUGACACCACGACUGGCUAACAACUUCCGUGCAAGGCCUUUACCUUAUACUUCCACACUACUGUAUGGACUACAGCAACCAAGAUGGCACCAUUGCACAGAAGCAAGCCACCAUCACUAGCAAGUUGGCCACUGUGAAAAGUGGCUGCUGUGCCUACUUCACUAGGUGACAGACAGACACCAUUGCUGGGUCAUGGAAAACAAGAUGUCACCAUGAUUGGUGGCACCAAAAGUGCCGUAACAGGGUGGGCAUGGUGGCUCACACCUGUAAUCCUAGGGAGGGUUAAUCCUUUCAGAGGCCAAGGUGGG